AAACCCUGGAUUUGCAACAUCCUCAAAGAACAGCAACGGGCCUUGAGCAGAAUUGAGAAGGAAAUACCCCCACCUGCCCUCAGCCGUUAAGUGGGCUUUGCUAUUCACAAGGGCCUCUGGGUGUCCUGGCAGAGAGGGGAGAUGGCACAGGCACCAGGUGCUAGGGUGCCAGGGCCUCCCGAGAAGGAACAGGUGCAAAGCAGGCAAUUAGCCCAGAAGGUAUCCGUGGGGCAGGCAGCCUAGAUCUGAUGGGGGAAGCCACCAGGAUUACAUCAUCUGCUGACCGGCAGGUGCAUACAAUGGCAAGGCCACCUGAUACACCAGUCCUGUUCAUUUGGAAAAGGGACAACUCCUUCACAUUCACAAGCUGGGCUGUAACAACUGCUCUGAAAAGAAGAUAUUUUUCAACCUGAACUUGCAGUAGCUAGUGGAGAGGCAGGUAAGGAAAAAGGAAAUGAAACCAGAGACAGAGGGAAGCUGAGCGAAAAUAGACCUUCCCGAGAGAGGAGGAAGCCCGGAGAGAGACGCACGGUCCCCUCCCCGCCCCUAGGCCGCCGCCCCCUCUCUGCCCUCGGCGGCGAGCAGCGCGCCGCGACCCGGGCCGAAGGUGCGAGGGGCUCCGGGCGGCCGGGCGGGCGCACACCAUCCCCGCGGGCGGCGCGGAGCCGGCGACAGCGCGCGAGAGGGACCGGGCGGUGGCGGCGGCGGGACCGGGAUGGAAGGGAGCGCGGUGACUGUCCUUGAGCGCGGAGGGGCGAGCUCGCCGGCGGAGCGCCGGAGCAAGCGGAGGCGCAGGAGCGGCGGCGACGGCGGCGGCGGCGGCGGCGCCCGAGCACCCGAGGGGGUCCGAGCCCCGGCAGCCGGCCAGCCCCGCGCCACAAAGGGAGCGCCCCCGCCGCCCGGCACCCCGCCUCCCUCCCCAAUGUCCUCGGCCAUCGAAAGGAAGAGCCUGGACCCUUCAGAGGAACCAGUGGAUGAGGUGCUGCAGAUCCCCCCAUCCCUGCUGACAUGCGGCGGCUGCCAGCAGAACAUUGGGGACCGCUACUUCCUGAAGGCCAUCGACCAGUACUGGCACGAGGACUGCCUGAGCUGCGACCUCUGUGGCUGCCGGCUGGGUGAGGUGGGGCGGCGCCUCUACUACAAACUGGGCCGGAAGCUCUGCCGGAGAGACUAUCUCAGGCUUUUUGGGCAAGACGGUCUCUGCGCAUCCUGUGACAAGCGGAUUCGUGCCUAUGAGAUGACAAUGCGGGUGAAAGACAAAGUGUAUCACCUGGAAUGUUUCAAAUGCGCCGCCUGUCAGAAGCAUUUCUGUGUAGGUGACAGAUACCUCCUCAUCAACUCUGACAUAGUGUGCGAACAGGACAUCUACGAGUGGACUAAGAUCAAUGGGAUGAUAUAGGCCCGAGUCCCCGGGCAUCUUUGGGGAGGUGUUCACUGAAGACGCCGUCUCCAUGGCAUCUUCGUCUUCACUCUUAGGCACUUUGGGGGUUUGAGGGUGGGGUAAGGGAUUUCUUAGGGGAUGGUAGACCUUUAUUGGGUAUCAAGACAUAGCAUCCAAGUGGCAUAAUUCAGGGGCUGACACUUCAAGGUGACAGAAGGACCAGCCCUUGAGGGAGAACUUAUGGCCACAGCCCAUCCAUAGUAACUGACAUGAUUAGCAGAAGAAAGGAACAUUUAGGGGCAAGCAGGCGCUGUGCUAUCAUGAUGGAAUUUCAUAUCUACAGAUAGAGAGUUGUUGUGUACAGACUUGUUGUGACUUUGACGCUUGCGAACUAGAGAUGUGCAAUUGAUUUCUUUUCUUCCUGGCUUUUUAACUCCCCUGUUUCAAUCACUGUCCUCCACACAAGGGAAGGACAGAAAGGAGAGUGGCCAUUCUUUUUUUCUUGGCCCCCUUCCCAAGGCCUUAAGCUUUGGACCCAAGGAAAACUGCAUGGAGACGCAUUUCGGUUGAGAAUGGAAACCACAACUUUUAACCAAACAAUUAUUUAAAGCAAUGCUGAUGAAUCACUGUUUUUAGACACCUUCAUUUUGAGGGGAGGAGUUCCACAGAUUGUUUCUAUACAAAUAUAAAUCUUAAAAAGUUGUUCAACUAUUUUAUUAUCCUAGAUUAUAUCAAAGUAUUUGUCGUGUGUAGAAAAAAAAACAGCUCUGCAGGCUUAAUAAAAAUGACAGACUGAAA